GUGGUCCCGGCGCCGGGUCCCGGAGACAGACGUUACGCGGGCUCGAGCGUCCUCGGGGAGUGCCAGCCAGAGUUGGUGACGACCACUUCCUCGACGUGGGGCGGGCGGACGGGAAGCCUGGGGUCGUGGCCACCGCCUCGGGAGCUCUGGGAGCCCGGGUGACCGCGUAGGUCAGUUUCUCGCGGCUGUCCACGCCUGGAGUUCGAGGCCGGUUCCCGCGCUGACGGGUUCCCGCCGGGCUGCGCUCGGGAGGUCUGUCCGCGCCUGGUUGGGGGUGGGCGCUCCCGUCCCGGGCGUCUCAGAGGAUGGUCGGGUCGUGGCGCGGCGACGCAGGGCUGCAGCCGAGCUCGGCUUCCCGGCGGCCGCUGGCUGCUCCAGCGCUGCAGGAAGUUAGGCGUUAAAAGUAACAAGAUGUUGGCGUUUGUUGCACUUCCCACUCGGGUGCCACGACCAUGCUGGUGCCGCAUGCAUCCCCUACCAGAUCUUCAGCUGCGUGCCUUCUCGAAAUGAACACAGAAGCGGAGCAACAGCUUCUCCAUCACGCCAGAAAUGGCAAUGCUGAAGAAGUAAGACAACUAUUAGAGACCAUGGCGAGGAAUGAAGUGAUUGCUGACAUUAAUUGCAAAGGAAGAAGUAAGUCUAACUUGGGCUGGACACCUCUACAUCUGGCAUGCUAUUUUGGACACAGACAAGUGGUCCAGGAUCUGUUGAAGGCUGGUGCAGAAGUGAAUGUGUUGAAUGACAUGGGAGACACGCCGCUUCAUCGAGCUGCCUUUACAGGACGAAAGGAGUUGGUAAUGCUUCUCUUAGAAUAUAAUGCUGAUACUACUAUUGUUAAUGGGAGUGGACAGACAGCAAAAGAAGUUACUCAUGCUGAAGAAAUCAGAAGCAUGCUUGAAGCUGUAGAAAGGACUCAACAAAGAAAGCUUGAAGAAUUACUUUUAGCAGCAGCAAGAGAAGGCAAAACAACAGAACUCACAGCUCUGCUCAACAGGCCCAAUCCUCCUGAUGUUAACUGUUCGGAUCAGUUAGGAAAUACACCCUUGCAUUGUGCAGCUUACCGGGCCCAUAAACAAUGUGCCUUAAAGCUUCUAAGAAGUGGAGCAGACCCUAAUCUGAAGAACAAAAAUGAUCAGAAACCUCUUGACCUUGCCCAGGGUGCUGAAAUGAAACACAUUCUUGUUGGUAAUAAGGUCAUCUACAAAGCAUUGAAACGAUAUGAGGGCCCUCUCUGGAAGAGUUCAAGAUUUUUUGGCUGGAGAUUAUUCUGGGUAGUGUUAGAGCAUGGAGUCCUUUCAUGGUAUAGGAAACAGCCUGAUGCAGUUCAUAAUAUUUAUCGCCAGGGAUGCAAACACCUGACUCAAGCAGUAUGCACGGUAAAAUCCACUGAUAGCUGCCUCUUCUUUAUUAAAUGCUUUGAUGACACCAUUCAUGGCUUCCGGGUUCCUAAGAAUAGCCUUCAGCAGUCAAGAGAGGACUGGCUGGAAGCAAUAGAAGAACAUUCUGCUUACAGCACUCACUACUGUUCCCAGGACCAGCUGACUGAUGAGGAGGAGGAAGAUACGGUUUCUGCUGCAGACCUGAAGAAAUCAUUAGAGAAAGCACAGUCAUGCCAACAGCGACUAGAUAGGGAAAUUUCCAACUUUCUCAAAAUGAUUAAGGAGUGUGACAUGGCUAAAGAAAUGCUUCCAUCAUUUCUUCAGAAAGUUGAAGUUGUCUCAGAAGCUUCUAGAGAAACUUGUGUAGCUUUGACUGAUUGCCUUAAUCUCUUCACCAAACAAGAAGGGGUGAGGAAUUUUAAAUUGGAACAAGAGCAAGAAAAAAACAAAAUCUUGUCAGAAGCACUGGAGACGCUGGCCACUGAACAUCAUGAAUUAGAGCAGUCUCUGGUGAAAGGCUCUCCACCCGCCAGCAUCCUUAGCGAGGACGAGUUCUAUGAUGCGCUGUCAGAUUCCGAGUCCGAAAGGUCCCUGAGUAGAUUGGAAGCAGUGACAGCACGCUCCUUUGAAGAGGAAGGAGAGCAUUUGGGCAGUAGAAAACACAGAAUGUCCGAAGAAAAAGACUGUGGUGGCGGAGAUGCUCUCUCCAAUGGCAUCAAGAAACACAGAACAAGUUUGCCUUCUCCUAUGUUUUCCAGAAAUGACUUCAGUAUCUGGAGCAUCCUCAGAAAAUGUAUUGGAAUGGAACUAUCCAAGAUCACGAUGCCAGUUAUAUUUAAUGAGCCUCUGAGCUUCCUACAGCGCCUAACUGAAUACAUGGAGCAUACUUACCUCAUCCACAAGGCCAGUUCACUCUCUGAUCCUGUGGAAAGGAUGCAGUGUGUAGCUGCGUUUGCUGUAUCUGCUGUUGCUUCUCAGUGGGAACGGACUGGAAAACCUUUCAACCCACUGCUGGGAGAGACUUAUGAAUUAGUGCGAGAUGACCUUGGAUUUAGACUCAUCUCCGAACAGGUCAGCCAUCACCCACCAAUCAGUGCAUUUCAUGCUGAAGGAUUAAACAAUGACUUCAUCUUUCAUGGCUCUAUCUAUCCCAAACUGAAAUUCUGGGGGAAGAGUGUAGAAGCAGAACCCAAAGGAACCAUCACCUUGGAGCUCCUUGAACACAAUGAGGCAUAUACAUGGACAAAUCCCACCUGCUGUGUGCAUAAUAUCAUUGUGGGUAAACUGUGGAUCGAACAGUAUGGCAAUGUGGAAAUUAUAAACCACAAGACUGGGGACAAAUGUGUGUUGAAUUUUAAGCCAUGUGGCCUUUUUGGUAAGGAAUUACACAAAGUUGAAGGCUACAUUCAAGAUAAAAGCAAAAAGAAGCUCUGUGCCCUCUAUGGGAAGUGGACUGAAUGUUUAUACAGUGUUGACCCUGCCACGUUUGACGCUUACAAAAAAAAUGAUAAGAAAAAUACAGAAGAGAAGAAGAACAGCAAACAGAUGAGCACCUCUGAGGAGUUGGAUGAAAUGCCAGUGCCGGAUUCUGAAAGUGUAUUCAUUAUCCCUGGAAGCGUUCUUCUAUGGCGAAUAGCCCCACGGCCUCCAAAUUCUGCCCAGAUGUAUAAUUUUACUAGUUUUGCAAUGGUUUUGAAUGAAGUAGACAAAGACAUGGAGAGUGUGAUUCCCAAGACAGACUGCAGGUUACGGCCUGACAUCAGAGCCAUGGAAAAUGGAGAGAUAGAUCAAGCUAGUGAAGAAAAAAAACGACUUGAGGAAAAACAAAGAGCAGCCCGCAAAAACAGGUCCAAGUCAGAAGAGGACUGGAAGACGAGGUGGUUCCAUCAAGGUCCUAAUCCCUACAAUGGAGCACAGGACUGGAUUUACUCUGGCAGCUACUGGGACAGAAAUUACUUCAAUUUGCCUGACAUUUAUUAAAAUGCAUACAAGUCAGGGUGUUUGGCUAAUCUACAAAUAAGUCUUAAACCUAUGUUUUUAAAUUUUUUUCCCUUGGUUUCUACUUAUCUUUUAAAAAAAAAAAUGAAAAAACACUCAUGAGAUAACUGCAUUUCACCCAACAAAAGCAGGGUAUAAGGCGAUAUUGGUGAUGAAAGUCUUAGGAAAAAUGCAUAAUUUUGCUAUAAAAUGUACUUAUUUGGAAUACUAUUUUAUAUAGAGGUAAGAGAACACUGCUGGGGAAUAUGCUUUUUAUGGUUGCUGUUGCCAUAUUUACUGAAGGUUUAUACCUAAAUGUAACUUUAGCUUUAUGGAACUAUAUAGUAAUCCCAAAUCAAGUUAUUUUGAAUAUUUUUAUGCUGUCAUGCUUGAAUGUUUUAGAUGUAACCUUUGACAUAUUUAGAACUCUCCUCCUAUACAAUGUUUAUUCUCAGAUAUAGAGGUUAUGUCAUUUUAUAAAGACUUCAUUGAUAAGAUGGCUUUUAUUCAUACUAAUCCUCCCAAUGUUACCCCUUCCAUCUUCCAAGAAGAAAAAAAAUGCCUGAAUAUUCAGAAUAGAUAUUUCUGAUUUGAAAAUUCUAAAGAAUUAAACUGGAAAAGUAUUUCAUUUACUUAGUGCUCUGAAUUUACUUUUACAGUUUUCUGCAGUCAGUAUCAUUAAAAUGGUUAAGUUUACAUUUGAACUGAAAAUAUGUAUAAAAUCUAGCAAUUCACAAAAAUGCCCUAGAAAUAUAGAUUUUAAUCACCAUUACAUAAUGACAAACCUUGUUAAAUGCUUCCACUUCCAGUGGCAAAUGCCACUAGGGAAAGUAAGUUGCACUCAUGUAAGUAUCAAACUAUAUAAAAGGAGGCCUUGUGCAUUUCAAGUUUGCAAAGUACCUGUGUACUUAAAAUAUGUGUGGAGACCUACUGUACAGUAGUUUUGCCCCUUUAAUUGGGGCACAUUCAUCUUAAAUCUUAUAGUAUUUAUCCACCCAAACCCCAGACUGAGAUACUGCUCCCAGGGGCCUAGGUAGCUGCCAGUCCGUGAUUUUAAUUGCUGUCUUGAAGUUAACAAGUGUUAUAAUGAAAUAAUCUACCUGAUGCUAAAUAAAGGCUUUAGAAUGUUCCCCAAAA